GGCUUCGGGUGUCAGCUGCUCUGUUUUGCUCAUGCACCUGCUUGUGCUUCUGUUGUUGCCUCCUCUCCCUGGCUGGGCUCGAGCUGCUUCAGGGCAGGAACCACGUCUUUAUAGUUUGAUGUUCCCAGAGCUGACCCAGUGUUUGGCAUAGGGGUGUGCUCAAUAAAAUCGAGUUGACAUGAAUGAGCAGAUGCUGCCUCGUUGCAGUCUGGUAGUGUAAUUCCAGGCUGCGCAUGUGAACUUCGACUUCUGCCCCUGCCCAGGGCAGAGACCACCGUGUUGCUUUAUGCCUCGCUGGUGAGAGGGGGUCAUAAACAGUUUGUGCUCCAUGAACCCUUCCUGCCCGCCUCCGAGGUCAUGUUUCUGCUCCCUCUCUUCUCCCUUAGAGCCCGUGGGGACAAGGCAGAGAACUUGAGUGGAGAUGGAGGUGGUGAAUAUUAAAGGAACAAAGUGCUCCUUCAGGUCUGGGCAAGAGCCAUGGAUCCUGUAGGUCAGCUUCUGGGGCUUCCCAUGCCCUCACGUUUCAGGAGAUAACGUGAGCCUCGGAGGACCUGAGUUCUGAAUAGAAAAUUUUUGCUCUUCAUUUCUUCACACACCCAGCCUCUCAGUGAGCUCCUGCUGGCUUUGUCCAGCAUGCGACAUAAGAUUGAAUCCAAGCCUUUUAAGAUAGAGCCGCCUGCUCUUUAGUGACCAUGAAGCCAAGCCUGUAAUAAUUACUCUUCUGAUAGCCCAAGACAAUUGUAUUCUGUUUUGUUAGAAAGGAAUUUCGAGGUGAACAAAAAUGUUUUCUUUUUAUGUGAUGUUGCCAUAGGUAGCGUGUGCCUGUCAGAUGGUUUUGUGUUUUCUGAGGAGCAUAGACUAGUAGAGCUAGCUCAGCUUCAGGCCAUGGGAUGCAGGGCUGGCUUCCCUGCCAACGCCUGGCGCUGAUGGAUUCUUCCCGCAUUGCUGGGAAGGGCAGACUGAGGCACUGACACAAGAAGAGUUGUAGCUGGUCAUAAGUGACAGCAUCCUCUGUUCACUCGAUUGGUCAGUUGUAGCUUCAUCCAGGAGAUGGUCAUGGGGUUCCUGCUGCAUACCAAGCUCUAGAGUGGAUGAGGAUGAGGAUGACCUGGAGGAAGAACACAUAACUAAGAUUUAUUACUGUAGUCGGACACACUCCCAGCUGGCCCAGUUUGUGCAUGAGGUGAAGAAGAGCCCCUUUGGCAAGGAUGUUCGGCUGGUCUCCCUUGGCUCCCGGCAGAACCUUUGUGUAAAUGAAGACGUGAAAAGCCUAGGUUCUGUGCAGCUUAUCAACGACCGCUGUGUGGACAUGCAGAGAAGCAGGCACGAGAAGAAGAAAGGAGCUGAGGAGGAGAAGCCAAAGAGGAGGAGGCAGGAGAAGCAGGCAGCCUGCCCCUUCUACAACCACGAGCAGAUGGGCCUUCUCCGGGAUGAGGCCCUGGCAGAGGUGAAGGACAUGGAGCAGCUGCUGGCCCUUGGGAAGGAGGCCCGGGCCUGUCCCUAUUACGGGAGCCGCCUUGCCAUCCCUGCAGCCCAGCUGGUGGUGCUGCCCUAUCAGAUGCUGCUGCAUGCGGCCACUCGGCAGGCCGCGGGCAUCCGGCUGCAGGACCAGGUGGUGAUCAUCGACGAGGCGCACAACCUGAUCGACACCAUCACGGGCAUGCACAGCGUGGAGGUCAGCGGCUCCCAGCUCUGCCAGGCCCAUUCCCAGCUGCUGCAGUACGUGGAGCGAUACGGGAAGCGUUUGAAGGCCAAGAACCUGAUGUACCUGAAGCAGAUCCUGUAUUUGCUGGAGAAAUUCGUGGCUGUGCUAGGGGGGAACAUUAAGCAAAAUCCCAAUACACAGAGUCUGUCACAGACAGGGACGGAGCUGAAGACCAUCAACGACUUUCUCUUCCAGAGCCAGAUCGACAACAUCAACCUGUUCAAGGUGCAGCGAUACUGUGAGAAGAGCAUGAUCAGCAGAAAGCUCUUUGGAUUCACUGAACGGUACGGAGCAGUGUUCUCAUCCCGGGAGCAGCCCAAACUGGCUGGGUUUCAGCAAUUCCUGCAGAGCCUGCAGCCCAGGACGACUGAAGCUCUUGCAGCCCCUGCAGACGAGAGUCAGGCCAGCACCCUGCGACCAGCUUCUCCACUGAUGCACAUCCAAGGCUUCCUGGCAGCUCUCACUACGGCCAACCAGGACGGCAGGGUCAUCCUGAGCCGCCAAGGCAGCCUCAGUCAGAGCACCCUGAAGUUUUUGCUCCUGAAUCCAGCUGUGCACUUUGCCCAAGUGGUGAAGGAAUGCCGGGCAGUGGUCAUUGCGGGGGGUACCAUGCAGCCGGCUGCAGGAGCAGUGGAGACUCCUCUGCUGCUCCAUUCUGUAGCCCCAGGAUCACAUGUCUCCCAGAGAAAGCUGUUCUGUGGUUUCAAACUCAAGGAAAAAAAUCAUGAUUCCACUUUUAAAAGGUGUCUGACUUCCGGCAGCAGCUGCUGGCCUGUGCCGGGGUGGAAGCUGAGCGCGUGGUGGAGUUUUCCUGUGUGUCUUGCAGCACACCUGCAUCUCCAGUUUUCGGCCCCUCCCUGGCUCUUACCAGGUCACGUGAUCCCUCCAGACAACAUCCUGCCCCUCGUCAUCUGCAGCGGGAUCUCCAACCAGCCGCUGGAAUUCACGUUCCAGAAAAGAGAGCUGCCUCAGAUGAUGGACGAGGUGGGUCGCAUUCUCUGUAACCUGUGCGGUGUGGUUCCUGGAGGGGUGGUCUGUUUCUUCCCCUCCUACGAGUACCUGCGCCAGGUCCAUGCCCACUGGGAGAAGGGUGGCCUGCUGGGCCGUCUGGCUGCCAGGAAGAAGAUAUUCCAGGAACCUAAGAGCGCACACCAGGUGGAGCAGGUGCUGCUGGCAUAUUCCAGGUGCAUCCAGGCCUGUGGCCAGGAGAGAGGCCAGGUGACAGGGGCCCUGCUCCUCUCUGUGGUUGGAGGAAAGAUGAGUGAAGGGAUCAACUUCUCUGACAACCUAGGCCGGUGUGUGGUGAUGGUGGGCAUGCCCUUCCCCAACAUCAGGUCUGCAGAGCUGCAGGAGAAGAUGGCCUACUUGGAUCAAACCCUCAGCCCCCGGCCAGGCACCCCCAGGGAAGGCUCUGGUGGAGAACCUGUGCAUGAAGGCCGUCAACCAGUCCAUAGGCAGGGCCAUCAGGCACCAGAAGGAUUUUGCCAGCGUAGUGCUCCUGGACCAGCGAUAUGCCCGGCCCCCUGUCCUGGCCAAGCUGCCGGCCUGGAUCCGAGCCCGUGUGGAGGUCAAAGCUACCUUUGGCCCCGCCAUUGCUGCUGUGCAGAAGGUCAGUCCUACCUUUUUCUUUCUGAGAGCCUCCCCACCCCGAGAUCACAUUUCUCACUGCCUUCUGUCUGCCCAGUUUCACCGGGAGAAGUCGGCCUCUUCCUGAUGGGCAACCACACCACUGCCUGGCGCCGUGCCCUUCCUUUGUCCUGCCCGCUGGAGACAGUGUUUGUCGUGGGCGUGGUCUGCGGGGAUCCUGUUACAAAGGUGAAACCCAGGAGGAGAGUGUGGAGUCCAGAGUGCUGCCAGGACCCAGGCACAGGCGUUAGCUCCCGUAGGAGAAAAUGGGGGAAUCCUGAAUGAACAGUGGGUCCUGGCUGUCCUUGGGGCGUUCCAGGGCAGCUCCCCUCCUGGAAUAGAAUCUUUCUUUCCAUCCUGCAUGGCUGAGAGCCAGGCUUCCUUCCUGGUCUCCGCAGGAGGCUGUGGCAGCUGUGGCAUCCACUGUGGCAUCUCCGUCCUGCCCACCUUCUUAAGAGGCGAGAUGGAGCAGGCCCAUCUGCCUCUGCCCUUUCUAGCCAAGGUUAUAGCUGCCCUGGACUGCUCACUCUCUGGUCUCAAUUUAAAAUGAUCCAUGGCCACAGGGCUCCUGCCCAGGGGCUUGUCACCUUCCCCUCCUCCUUCCUGAGUCACUCCUUCAGUAGAAGGCCCUGCUCCCUAUCCUGUCCCACAGCCCUGCCUGGAUUUGUAUCCUUGGCUUCGUGCCAGUUCCUCCAAGUCUAUGGCACCUCCCUCCCUCUCAACCACUUGAGCAAACUCCAAGACACCUUCUACCCCAACACCAGCAAUUAUGCCAAGGGCCGUUAGGCUCUCAACAUGACUAUAGAGACCCCGUGUCAUCACGGAGACCUUUGUUCCUGUGGGAAAAUAUCCCUCCCACCUGCAACAGCUGCCCCUGCUGACUGCGCCUGUCUUCUCCCUCUGACCCCAGAGAAAGGGGCUGUGGUCAGCUGGGAUCUUCUGCCACCAUCAGGGACAAACGGGGGCAGGAGGAAAGUCACUGAUGCCCAGAUGUUUGCAUCCUGCACAGCUAUAGGUCCUUAAAUAAAAGUGUGCUGUUGGUUUCUGCUGA